UGAGGUGCACGGGAGCCCGCCGGCCUCUCUCUGCCCGCGUCCGUCCGUGAAAUUCCGGCCGGGGCUCACCGCGAUGGCCCUCCCGACACCCUCGGACAGCACCCUCCCCGCGGAAGCCCGGGGACGAGGACGGCGACGGAGACUCGUUUGGACCCCGAGCCAAAGCGAGGCCCUGCGAGCCUGCUUUGAGCGGAACCCGUACCCGGGCAUCGCCACCAGAGAACGGCUGGCCCAGGCCAUCGGCAUUCCGGAGCCCAGGGUCCAGAUUUGGUUUCAGAAUGAGAGGUCACGCCAGCUGAGGCAGCACCGGCGGGAAUCUCGGCCCUGGCCCGGGAGACGCGGCCCGCCAGAAGGCCGGCGAAAGCGGACCGCCGUCACCGGAUCCCAGACCGCCCUGCUCCUCCGAGCCUUUGAGAAGGAUCGCUUUCCAGGCAUCGCCGCCCGGGAGGAGCUGGCCAGAGAGACGGGCCUCCCGGAGUCCAGGAUUCAGAUCUGGUUUCAGAAUCGAAGGGCCAGGCACCCGGGACAGGGUGGCAGGGCGCCCGCGCAGGCAGGCGGCCUGUGCAGCGCGGCCCCCGGCGGGGGUCACCCUGCUCCCUCGUGGGUCGCCUUCGCCCACACCGGCGCGUGGGGAACGGGGCUUCCCGCACCCCACGUGCCCUGCGCGCCUGGGGCUCUCCCACAGGGGGCUUUCGUGAGCCAGGCAGCGAGGGCCGCCCCCGCGCUGCAGCCCAGCCAGGCCGCGCCGGCAGAGGGGAUCUCCCAACCUGCCCCGGCGCGCGGGGAUUUCGCCUACGCCGCCCCGGCUCCUCCGGACGGGGCGCUCUCCCACCCUCAGGCUCCUCGGUGGCCUCCGCACCCGGGCAAAAGCCGGGAGGACCGGGACCCGCAGCGCGACGGCCUGCCGGGCCCCUGCGCGGUGGCACAGCCUGGGCCCGCUCAAGCGGGGCCGCAGGGCCAAGGGGUGCUUGCGCCACCCACGUCCCAGGGGAGUCCGUGGUGGGGCUGGGGCCGGGGUCCCCAGGUCGCCGGGGCGGCGUGGGAACCCCAAGCCGGGGCAGCUCCACCUCCCCAGCCCGCGCCCCCGGACGCCUCCGCCUCCGCGCGGCAGGGGCAGAUGCAAGGCAUCCCGGCGCCCUCCCAGGCGCUCCAGGAGCCGGCGCCCUGGUCUGCACUCCCCUGCGGCCUGCUGCUGGAUGAGCUCCUGGCGAGCCCGGAGUUUCUGCAGCAGGCGCAACCUCUCCUAGAAACGGAGGCCCCGGGGGAGCUGGAGGCCUCGGAAGAGGCCGCCUCGCUGGAAGCACCCCUCAGCGAGGAAGAAUACCGGGCUCUGCUGGAGGAGCUUUAGGA